CCCUGGGCCACGCCCCGGUCCCGGGUCACCUCUCGGAGCCGCCUCCUUGGCCCGUGGAAGCCUCCUGCUCUCCCCUAGGGCGCGCGUCACAAUCUCUGGUCCCCCGUAGACGCCGCCGCGGGGAAGGCGGGGCUGUGCGAGGGCGCCGCGCUGCAAACCCAAGCCAGGCGGCCUGGAGUUGCUGUAAAGCCUCAAGCAAGGCUGAUAUGUAAAAGGUCGUUGCAUUUCACCCGGGCUGUGGGCUGUGCUACUUGACCGGGGAGGACGAGGGGACUGCAGGGCGUCCUUUCAGACAGACGCGGUAGGGAGAGCAGGGCGUGCAGGACACUUGACGGCCCCAGGAGAGGGGUGAGGCCCUGACCCCACCGGGGUGUCAUCCAGGAGGAAGGGUGCCCGGGGCGAGGUCCCCCAGGAGAAGUGCCCAGGCCUGAGGCCUUGACCCCACUGAGAUGUCCCCCCAGGAGGAGGGGUGCCCGGGGUUAGCUCCCCUAGGAGGAGGGGUACCCGGGAGUGAGGCCCUGACCCCACCGCGAGGUCCCCCAGGAGGAGGGGUGCCCAGGAGUGAGGCCCUGACCCCACCAGGAGGUCCUCCAGGAGGAGGGGUGCCCAGGAGUGAGGCCCUCACCCCACCGUGAGGUCCCCCAGAAGGAGGGGUGCCCAGGAGUGAGACCCUGACCCCACCAGGAGGUCCCCCAGGAGGAGGGGUGCCCGGGAGUGAGGCCCUGACCCCACCGCGAGGUCCCCCAGGAGGAGGGGUGCCCAGGAGUGAGGCCCUGACCCCACCAGGAGGUCCCCCAGGAGGAGGGGUGCCCGGGAGUGAGGCCCUGACCCCACCGCGAGGUCCCCCAGGAGGAGGGGUGCCCAGGAGUGAGACCCUGACCCCACCAGGAGGUCCCCCAGGAGGAGGGGUGCCCGGGAGUGAGGCCCUGACCCCACCGCGAGGUCCCCCAGGAGGAGGGGUGCCCGGGAGUGAGGCCCUGACCCCACCGUGAGGUCCUCCAGGAGGAGGGGUGCCCGGGAGUGAGGCCCUGACCCCACCGUGAGGUCCCCCAGGAGAAGGGGUGCCUGGGGAAAGACAUGACCUCAGUAGCUCCGGGUACCCUCCACCUUUGCCCUCAUUUCCGCCUCCGCAUGCAGCCUUGGGAACUGCAGGGCUGGGAACCCGGAGAAGGCGGCCGGGCUCUGGGGGAGCUCAGAGGUGGCCUUCCCUGCCAGGAACACAGGCCAGGCCCCAUCCCUAUCUAACCUUAUACUUGAGGAGCACAGAGCGGAUAUCUCCAGAUUUGAGUCCUGAACGCGCGGCCGGGAACCCCAGCAGUUCUGAACUUGUCAAGGGAGCAGCCUGCCAUGAGGGGUCUCCCAGGCGGCUGUGAGGCCUCUGGAAACUCCCUGCUUGGAGGAGGUUGACUGGGGACAGGGCCGUGGGGGUCAAUAAAAAGGACUGCUGCCAUUAGCCCUGGGCUGCCUGCACACAGAGAUUAAGCCCGCUUGGGAUUUGUUCCAGCUGAUCUGAAGUAAUGAGUAAUUCACAAUUAAUGAGCAUGGCUGUAAGCAGCCCUUCCUGGACAAAUCCUUGGCUGUCCAAAACUAAGAUUAAAUGCAAAUCAUUCUGUCAAUUAACCGUUACAACAAAGCCAAACUUCUGUUAAGCAUCACUUCAUAGAUGGUUUUUUUUCCCUUAAAUUGCCUCCUUGUUUGCAAAGCCUGUUUUACAAGUGGACUGCUUAAGUCACAUGAGUGAAAAUGCAGCCUUAUUUACCGUUCAGCAAAAGCUAUCUGAGAAUUUGCUUCCAGGGACUUCAUGUUCUCCAGAGGUUGGGGUACUAGGAAUCAUUUCAUUGUAAAGGACUCAGUAAAAAGUAGCCCUGUAGCUGCCAGAAUGCGCCGUAGGCUCAUGAUAAGGUAGGUGGUAAGGGCCAGAGGUCAGGGGUCACAGAUGGCUUCUGCCCCUCCACAGCACAUGGUGUCCAGAACUGGGCUUGCCUCUCACCUUCCUUCCUGUACAUUUCCUGGUGCCAGAAAUUUGCUUUUCACUGACUUCCCCCUAAUUCAAAUUUGAUUAGAAUCUCCUUUUUGGGAACAUUCAAAGUGCCAAGGUGCGUUUCAGAAAUGCAGGGUUGCAGAGGUGGGGUCCUGAAAUCCAAGGGUGGUGGGGCCUGAGAUCACUGCCCUCGCAGUAGGAAGAUCCUCGGGGAGAGGUCAGCAGAGGGCCCGGACAGAAGGCACUGACACUGUACCCUGGAGAGAGACAGGAAGGAGGACCUGGGGCCUCAGAGCUGGCCGGGUGGAGAUCGUGUGGUCUUCGUUCAGAGGGAAGUGAGGUGCUGAUGAAAGAUGAUUGACGUCACGUGGGCACCAGCAGAGGAAGUGACACAAAACGCCCCACAGCUUUGGGUUCACUGAGUGGGCAGUUGUAUUUAUUUAUUUUAUUUUAUUUUUGUAGAGAUGGGGUCUUGCUGUUGCCCAGACUGGUCUCGAGCUCUUGGCCUCCCAAACUGCUGGGAUUACAAGUGAGAGCCAUUGCAGAUAGCCAGUUUUCUUUAUUUUUAAUUGUUGUUUGUGCAAAAGGUUUUGGCGAAUACUGGCUAUAUUCAGAGGACUCAGUACCAGUUGCCAGGGGCCUGGAGUAGGUGCUGUGGUCUCAAUGUGUGUGUCCCCCCAAACCAUAUGUUGACACCUAACCCCCAAGGCGAUGUGGUUAGGAGAUGGAGCUUUAAGGAGGUGACUGGGCCGUGAGGGCUGUCCUCUCAUGACGGACGAGUGCCCUUCAACGAGACUUGAAGGAGCCCUUCUGUCCCUUCCUCCACGUGAGGACACAUAGAAGGUACCAUCUCUGGGGAACAGGCUGUCACCAAACACCAAGUCUGCUGGCGCCUGGAUCCUGGACUUCUCAGCCUCUACAACUGUGUGCAAUACAUUUCUACUGUUUAUCAAUCACAUGGUCAGAGGUAUUUUGUUACAGCAGCACAAAUGGACCAAGACAUCAGGUCUCCAAAUCGAAGAACUUCUCAGCAGCCUUCAGUGCUGGGUGGGGAGACAGAGGUUCCCUGCAGGUCCCCACAGACAGUGUUAGACUCAGUGCUGGGUGGGGAGACAGAGGUUCCCUGCAGGUCCGCACGGACGGUGUUAGACUCGGUGCUGGGUGGGGAGACAGAGGUUCCCUGCAGGUCCGCACGGACGGUGUUAGACUCGGUGCUGGGUGGGGAGACAGAGGUUCCCUGCAGGUCCGCACGGACGGUGUUAGACUCGGUGCUGGGUGGGGAGACAGAGGUUCCCUGCAGGUCCCCACGGACAGUGUUAGACUCGGUGCUGGGUGGGGAGGUUCCCAGCAGGUCCGCACGGACGGUGUUAGACUCGGUGCUGGGUGGGGAGGUUCCCUGCAGGUCCGCACGGACGGUGUUAGACUCGGUGCUGGGUGGGUUGACAGAGGUUCCCUGCAGGUCCGCACGGACGGUGUUAGACUGGGUGCUGGGUGGGGAGGUUCCCUGCAGGUCCGCACGGACGGUGUUAAACUCGGUGCUGGGUGGGGAGGUUCCCUGCAGGUCCGCACGGACGGUGUUAGACUCGGUGCUGGGUGGGGAGACAGGUUCCCUGCAGGUCCCCACAGACAGUGUUAGACUCGGUGCUGGGUGGGGAGGUUCCCUGCAGGUCCGCACGGACGGUGUUAGACUCGGUGCUGGGUGGGGAGACAGAGGUUCCCUGCAGGUCCCCACAGACAGUGUUAGACUCGGUGCUGGGUGGGGAGGUUCCCUGCAGGUCCGCACGGACGGUGUUAGACUCGGUGCUGGGUGGGGAGACAGAGGUUCCCUGCAGGUCCGCACGGACGGUGUUAGACUCAGUGCUGGGUGGGGAGACAGAGGUUCCCUGCAGGUCCGCACAGAUGGUGUUAGACUCGGUGCUGGGUGGGGAGACAGAGGUUCCCUGCAGGUCCGCACGGACGGUGUUAGACUUGGGGGACACUGGGUCCCCAGUAAGAAUGAUUCUGAUGUGAGUGCAGCUAGUGAGGGCUGAGUUCAAGCUUUAAAGACAAGAGCCCAACAGGUUCCUUCAACAGCCUGAUCCCCUAGACCUUCGUGUGUCCAAGUCUCCAGAGGGGAUGAACCUCAACAGACCUGGUUCGACCUCCCCUAGGCAGUGGGUGCUGCCUGGAGGGCAGGGUCGCUCGAGACUGUAGGAGACUCUGCACGUGGUGACCAUAGCACCCCCAUAAUAAAGCAGCCCGUGAGGGCAGCCUGGCUGUUCGGCGAUGUGUGCACUGAGGUCAUCUCUCCUACUCUGUCUCAGCUAUUUAAAGGCUGUGACUCACCAUGUGGAUUUAAUGACUUAUUAAGGAGUUGCAGCCCAUGCUUUUUAAAAAAGUAAUCUACAAAAAAAUAAAUGAAAAAGUCUUCAGGACAGUAGACUUAAGUGCGGAUGUGGUCCCUCGAGUUCCAUUUUUCAGCCGCCCACAUUCCUGGGAUUCAGACCUGUUGGGGAUUGUAGGAUUCUAGUUGCACAGGGAAACCCAGAGUCAAUUCAGGAGGAUAAUUCUGAGCCAGGGGUGGGGGUACCGGCCUGGAGCUCCGGGGGGUACGGGCUGAUCCUACGAAAGGAAAGUCAAGCCUGUGAAUUGCAGAGCCUGGACAGAGAAGUUGAGGUGACGGCGUUCUGCAGAUCCGUGAAAUUCUAUUACACGUCAGAGGGAAGGGACGGCCUCAUGUGGCCCCUUGGAGGGACCAAGCCCUACCCAGCGCCUUGCCCAAGUCAGCACGCAGUCAGUGUUGGCUCCACCCACCUGCACCGUCAGGCCUUCUGGAAAGAGAAGGAGAUCCGACUGACGGAGCGUCUCCAAACUUCCAAGCAAAUAUUACCUCGUUAAAGCCCAGUGCCACAUGACUGACCUGGAGCCACAGCCUGCCCUCCUUCCCUGGGCCUACAGGAAGGGGGAGGUUCCUGUCACCAGAACCGUUCCGUCAUCAGCCGGGCAGAUGCUCGCUGUGGAUUCUAGGUGAGCAUCAAGUACUAGGGACCAUGUUUGUCUUGGAUUCCCCCGUCCCGCCUGAGCCCAGAACGCAGAGCCGGAGUCAGGGGCUUGCACAUGGAGCGUUUCACGCCCAGGAGGCUGGGGCAGGGGCCAGGAAGGAGCGGGGAGGGGGCCAGGACCAGCGUGCUCUGCUGAGGGUCCACAUCGAGGGCUGGACCCUGGACCUCCACAAGCCUGGAGAAUUCUCCAUCCGAGCAGUGAGGAGCCCCUGCUUGUUGUCAGCUGGAGCUGCGCCUCGGGGCUUCUGCUGUCCUGGCCCUGGGGUGGUGACUGCAGGAUCCCACAGGUGUCCCGAGGCCUGAGGCUCUUCUCACUGCAGAGGCCACCCUGCAGGAAUUGGAGUUAGGACCCGGAGGGUGGGACAGGCUGACUCAGAGGAGCCAGCUCUCAGGUUGGCAGGAGGAGGAGAUGCACAAUGAGACAGCAGCCUCACCUCCAGGGGACGGCCCCGCAAGCCGGAGCUGCCCUCCUGCACACUCAGCACUCAAGGUGGAUUUGGAGGUGACCUAAGCCCACAGCUCUCCAAGUCUUGGGGAAAUCUACAGUGGAUGGCAGGUGCCUGCGGACGCCGAGUGGGUGCGGCCCCAGUUAUGCUCAAUGCAGGGGCACCUGUGUUGUUAGCAGCUGACGUGGACGGGAAAGGCCUGUGCUGAACAACGUUCCGUGUUCAAUUAGACACUCUCCUCCUAAACAGGGGCGGAAGACGUCUCAUGGGGGUUCCAAGCGUGAUUUAUGGAACUCACUCCCAUGAGAUAACAUAACAUUUUUCACACGUGGGAGAAAGGGCUGGGCUCGACUGGUGCCUGAGUGAAUGCUGAGGAUAAAUGGGAAGCAGGACAUUCCAGGGCACCUCUGCGUCUUGCAUGAGACCUUGUGAGGGCCCUGUGGUGCCCCUGAUGUCACUGUCGAAGGUGGAGCCGCCCCCGCUCUGCCUCGGCCUCCCUCAGAUGUCCUCCCCAGCUGGCCCUGCAGCGCACGUGGAAGACAGCUGCCGAGAAGCAGGUGUGAUGCCAGCCUGUGGGAGAAGCCACAUCUGGACAGUGCGUGAAGCCAGUCCAGGGGCCACACCGGGACCUGCCCUCAGCUCUGCCACGUCCUGGCCAAGUGGCCUUGGCAUGCCAGCCCUGGUGUCCACAGAGGCAUCCAUUCCUCAUGGCAAAGUGGAGUCAAGUCGGCUGAUGCAGGCGAGACACCUGGCCGGCCUGGGGAGCCGCACCAGCGCUCCCCACAUUGCACUGCUGACUGAGGGGUGCUCGGUGCCGCGGCUUCACACGGUCAGUGCACAGACAUGAACGCUGGACUGAGAAGCCGCCGCGUGCACCUGGCCCGCCAAGUUGCCAGGGAGGCAAGGGUGGUGUUGACGUGGAUCACCGAAGGAGCUGGCAGCCCAGCCGUCCCCGUGACUGGAUGGAAUCCGCAAGCGUUCCUGGGCAUCCACUCUGGGAAGGGCUCAGUGCCAGGGCCUAGGGUAGUUUUCAAAUUGCAGGUUGUGGCCAGUAUACCAGGGGUCAUGGGGUCAGUACACUGGGCUCUGACUGGCAAUUCCUAAAGAUGAAGUGUGAGUCUGUCCCAUAUAGUAAGAGCUGCAUUGAUUUGUAAAGCUUGUGUUGGUUUUGCACGUUCUAUGCCAGUGUGUGCUGGACCGUGAUAGAAAGCGCAUUUCUCGCUGUGGUGCCUGCCGUAGUCUGGAGGGAAAGAUGAGUCCGUGGCUCUAAUGUGGGGUGGUGGGUGUGGUCUACACAGGGAGAGCGAAGAGCCCACAUGGGGCAUGAGAGGGGCCGGAGAGGCUGGGGCAGGGGAACCCGGGCCAGGUCCUGAGAACAAAUGGGGUUAUUCAGCUCCUAAAGGUGCAGGACUCAGCCCAAAGUCCCUGGUGACCCAAAGAGGACCAUGUGAGUCUGAUGUGGCUGUGGAAGGCGGGGCUCACAGCAGGCUGCCGGGGCACCAUUAAUGGGGGAGGGUCCUGUCCCCAGCGCAUACGUAGACGGCCCUUCAGAACCUGCUCAGUGGUCAGUGCGGCCGUGCAGCUGCACCCCGGCCUGGUCACCUGUGCUGUGCCCAGCAAGGAAGAUGCCCCCGCUCAGCCCGUCCAUGCACCCUCCAGAGGCUGUCAGCUGCCUGAGACCCACACUGGCUCUUGCAGGCUAGAGGAGAGUUCAAUGGCCAUUCGGGCCCUGUCGCCAUGGAAACACCAACUUUGGGUACCAAAAGCCUGAAUGUACAAAUUCAUGGAGUAUGACCUGCCUGGUGCCAGUGGGUCUUUGCAUUUUUCUGGGGUGCCAGUGGGUCUUUGCGUUUUUCUGGGGUGCCAGUGGGUCUUUGCGUUUUUCUGAUGCCCUCUGAACUCUUAGGUCCCGGUUCUGGCGGAUUUGGCCCAGGCACCCCCAGCCCCCAGGUAGGAGGCACAACCCUGCUCCCAAUGCCCAACACCUGCCCCCAAUGCCCAACACCUGCCCCACACACCUGAGGUACCUCCUGGGCGUCCCACACCAGGACAGGCCUGGAGACUUCCAGCCACUGCCACCUGGCACACCCAGCACCUGCAGAUCCACCACCUUAAAACCCACCUCUACUGCCCCAUGUCACGGUCCCUGCGGGGCCAGGCCUGCCUGGCACGUCCACCCCGGGUCUCCCUGCCUCACCCUCUUGCGCAUCCACAGUGAACAGGGGCAUCUUUCCAAAAUGCAGAUCUGGCCGGGUGCGGCGGCUCAUGCCUGUAAUCCCAGCACUUUGGGAGGCCGAAGCAGGUGGAUCACAUGAAGUCAGAAGUUGGAGACUAGCCUGGCCAACAUGCCAGCCUCCAGCAUCGCCUCCUCUGGGAUCUUCUCUGACUUCCCAGUCGGUUUCAGAAGCCUCUGAUGACCCCAUGCGGAGAAGACUGCUCCCCUCACUGCUGGCACACGGCAGAUGCUCAGUAAGUAUCGUUCAAUGACUGACUAAAUGUCUCAUAAUAUCCUUCAUAAACAAGGGCCUGGUGUGGAUUCAUAAAUGGGUCUCUCAAAGUUUAAUUGGUGAGACUCUGUUGUAUCAGACAAUGAAGGGUUAAAAGAUAAUAUUCAAAAAAGUAAAAUCAUGACACACAAAUCUAGAAUGAACACACAUUGAUAAGGUUUGGAUCUGUGUCCUCACCCAAACCUCAUGUCGAACUGGGAUCCCCCGUGUCAGAGGCGGCCGCGUGGGAGGUGACCGGAUCGCGGGUGGACCCUUCAUGAAGGGUUCAGCACCAUCCCCUUGGUGCUGUCCUGGGACAGAGUUCUCUUGCGAUCUGGUUGUUUAAACGUGUGUGGCCCCUUCCCCCUCUCUUUUCCUCCUCCUCCUGCCGUGGGAGACACUUGCUCCAGCUUCGCCUUCCGCCGCGAGUUGAAGCUCCCCGAGGCCUCCUCAGAAGCAGAAGCCACCACGCUUCCUGUACAGCCUGUGGGACCCGGAGCCAGUUCAACCUCUUUUCUUUAUAAAUUACCCAGACUCGGCCGGGCACGGUGGCUCACGCCUGUAAUCCCAGCACUUUGUUGAGACCGAGGCAGGCAGAUCACGAGGUCAGGAGAUCGAGAACAUCCUGGCUAACACGGUGAAACCCCGUCUCUACUAAAAAUACAAAAAAUUAGCCGGGCGUGGUGGCGGGCGCCUGUGGUCCCAGCUACUCGGGAGGCUGAGGCAGGAGAAUGGUGUGAACCCGGGAGGCGGAGCUUGCAGUGAGCCGAGAUCCCGCCACUGCACUCCAGCCUGGGCAGCAGAGCGAGACUCCAUCUCAACAAAUAAUAAUAAUAAAAUAAAUAAAUAAAUAAAUAAAUAAAUAAAUAAAU